GGGCUCCGCCCCCCGGGUAGGGACCUACAGCGGGCGCGGCGCCGGCGGUCUGCGGCCGGCGGUGUAGACGCCCCUUCGCCGGGACCUGGCACCCGAAUCCGGCCUGCCGGGCCUCUUUGUGCAGCGCCUUGCUGACGCCCAGGGUUCUGAUGUAGAAGCCUACACCAGGGCCUGAGGUUGUGAAACUCAUGGCAGUCCACGCCUGAGAAGAGAAGGCCUGAAAGAGAAGGAAGAGCCCAUGGGACUUGCCACGGUUUUGACUUACAUCUGCAACUCCAAGGCUACAGGCAGGAAGUAAGAACAGUGCUCAAGUGGCAGCAGAUACUGACUAUGGCUUCAUUUCACAGCUUCACACAGCAGGGUAGCAGAAAACAAAGAAUGUAAGAUUGGACCCAGUUGCAGCUGUUCACCAACUCUGUGAUCUUCAAAAAGCCAUAUAGCUUCUCCAGACCUGUUAAUCAGGGAAGAAGCAGAUAACUGAAGGCUGGCUUUGAGAAGUUUCGAGACUCAGUUGAUGUGCACAGCAGUGUCAAGUCAAUCUCCAAAAUACUCCCUGUAGACAGGGUGGGGAGAAGACCCUCACUUCCUGCCGACUAAUGAACUCAUGUUGAUACAGACCUUUGCCUCAUCAGAUUCAUUUGUUAAGCUAACCAGUGUCUGCUUCUCUGGACAUUACUGGACUCUUCUACCUGUGAAGCCAUCUUAAAAAAAUAUAUUGACUGAUUUCUUAACGAAACAUCUACUCUUUGCCAAGCAUAAAGUUACCUCCCACUUGCAUACACCCUUUUCUCAUUUGUCCUCACAUCAGCUGUAUAAAUGAGAAAUAUUCACAUUUUAUAAGUGAGAACAUUCAGGCUCAGAUAGGUUAACAAGUUUGAAAUCAUGUGCUAGUAAACCAAACACCUAGGUUUUGAACCUUGUUCUUCUUGUCCCAAGGUCAUUAUUCUCUACUGUGUUACACUCAGCUGCUUUCACCUGGAAAAGCAGAGGAAUCAGGCUGUCUCCUGCAGCUGUCUUGGUCCAUUCUGCUGCCCAAGCAGUACACUUGGUUUCAGAUGGAAAUCUAGGAUCCCAAGCAUGGGUACAUUUGUCGGCAGCAUUUGGAAGUAUUUUUCGUCAUCAGGAUGGCAGUCAAUUUGCAAUUCAGUCAUCUCAGUGCAAGGUAGUUUGGCAAAAAGAUUAUGACACUUAAUGGAUUUUUUUCCUCUUUUAAAUCUGUUUACCCAGCAUUUUGUAGUAUAAUGCAAUGUAAUAACAUUGCAUUAUUUUGAGCAUAGUUUAGAAGCCAAGAAGAUGCUUUCAAACAGCUGACAUAAUUCAGUUAUGGCCCAGAUGUCCUGCCUUCCCCAUCACACAUUCAUAUUAAUGGUCUUAGAAAGCUGUUUCUGAGGCAACAGUUUCUUCCUCAAUAUCAUCCUACUGGGGAAAUUUUGGCAGUUGAUGUCUAAUGUUGAUUUUUUUUUCCUGAUUGAUUUUAAUUGUUCACUGGGCACUUUGGGGUAGAAUUGUUUUAAAAAUUUGGUUACUGGGAAAGCUAGACAAGCCUUUGCUAUGGUGAAAGAGACAGAAGGAAUAUAGAUAUAAUUUGUAAGUGGUUAUGCCAUUGGGCUUAAUGCUUUGCAUACAUUAUCUAGUUUGCAUCUCCUGAUCGCCCUUUAAGUUUGCUUACGGUAAAGCAUUAUUCCUUGCUUGGCAAUGCACAGAGAAAAAUUAUUUGCUGAAGGACCCUGCAAAUGAGGGACAGGAUCAGAGUUGGAACUGUAAACCCUGCCACUCCAUUUCAUGUGAUCUUCAUGGGUACAGCAGCUAUACCCUGCCCCAGCAAUGAGUAUGGUAGAGCCACAUUCAAAGGCGGACUUUGGGGUCAGCAUUCCUGAAAAGAGCUGCUUAAGUUUGCUUCUACAUCCAAAAACGAUGCAGUCACAGUCAACUAACACUGAGCUUGCUGGGCAUCUCCUGAACAGAAAUGUAUGUGGUGGUCCAUGUAGCAUGUAUGCGAUAUAAUUGGCCACCCACCUUUCCUUUUCACAUUAACAUUUAUCACAGAAACACAUUCAUUUGCUACAGGGAUAUUUCACAAUUUGGCUGAACUUUGAGAGAAGUGGGUGAGGAAAAGGUAGUUUCGUAACUAGUUUAUAUAUAAACCUAAAUUGUAGUGAGUACUCUUGUAAGUGGAGCAUCUUUUCUAUGGUAAUUAUAAAUGGCUGUUAGCCCCUUUGCACUAAAGCUAGGUGGGUGGUUUUGCCACAGAGGUAAAUUAUCUUUCGGGCGGUAUAACCAAACAAAUAAAAUAUAAAGUGAGAUUCAGGGCAUGUUCUGAAUACAGCAGUUAAUUAGGCAGCUAAGAAAACUGUAUUUUAGCCCCUCUGACUAUGUGAUUGGUAUUUUUUUAAAUUAAAAAAUGGAAAAUAAUAUUUUUAACAGGUUAUGAUAUGUCAGUCAUUUAAUCCUCACAGUAACUCUGUGGGGUAGGUAGGUACUGUUUCUAUCUCAUUUUACAGGUAAGGAAUCAAAACAGUGGGUAUACCCAGGUUGUAUAUCUAGAAAGUGAUAGAGCUGGGAUUUUAAACUUUAUAAUCUGAUUCCAGAAUCUCUACCUUUAAACACUAUGUUACCACUUACUUCUCUUCAAAUUUUAUUGAGCAUUAGAUGUUUCCAGUAUUUAGAAGUCAAAUGCUUCGUUUUUAAUAGGAACUUACACAGUCUUUUAUGUUUUUUUAUAGCCCUCAAUGUCACUGAUGUGGAUUCUCCCAAACUCGAUACUUUGUUUGUUUUUAUGUCCCCAUAAUAAGUCUUUAAGAAAACAGGGCAAGUGAGCUCAAAAUCAAAAGAAAACCCACCAACAGUGAAUGCAUUCAGGGCUAUUUCCAGGUCUUUCUUUUGAAGAAAGAUAAGACUCAGUCCAGAGAGCACAUCUGUGACACACCGUGCCUCUUGCCUUUGGUGCGUGGCAGUCAUCUUUGGCUCAUGCUGUACCUUAUUCUACAUUAGAAAACUCACUGUAUGUUGCUAAAUAAUUUUUUGAAAACAGGCAGAUUAAUAAAUGGACAUCUUAUUUAUUGCACCAUAAAAUUAAUGGUAUUCUUUUCUGUGUUUUCGAGACCUUUCCUAAGCUAUCUGAAAGUCCUAAGACGCCAAAUGCAGAGGCUUUUGCAACAGAUGUUGAGAGUUUGCACGGUAGGCAAACACUGACCCUGCUGUUAAUAGUAAUUUAUUGAGUACCCUUUCAGUGCCAGCAUACCCAUGCACAGCUUUGUCUCCGGUGUCUUUUUGUACUCCUUGGUCAUCCAUCCAGAGAGUCAUAACUUGCCAAGAGGACUCAGCUUCACAGUGUUACCUGGAAUGUCAGAGAGCUGAAAGCAGUCAUAUUUUGGGAUCAUGCACCUACUGCGGCAGUAUAUAAAGAAAGAUAAUUAAGUAUGCACCCAAGAAGUAGCUGCGCCCCUACCCAUCACAAACUGUAUAGAAGGAUAUCUCCUAAGGAUUUUAUCAUGUGAAAACUUUCUGAAUUUUAGUUGGCUCUUUUUAGAAAUGCAGAUAAGAUGAAGGAUAUUGGACAGCAGCUAUACACUACACACUUGAACGGCGGACAUAAUUCCUUGACCAUGUCACCCAAACAGCCUGAUGCUAAUGGAGCACCUCGGCCAAAUAGACAAGAAGCACAAACCCUUUUGUAUCAAGGCUCAGAGGCAGAGGCUGCCAUGAUGACCAUUGCUACAUGUGCAAAGUGCAAAAGUGUUCACAAGAUCUCUCUUCAAGAUUUGCAGAAGGGUACAGGGAAGGACGGUAUGUAUGUCUGCUUCCAGUGCAGCCUCGGUGCAGCUCCUCCCAAUUUUCAUUUUGUGAGCAAUAAUUCCAGUGCGACUCAUGUUGGAAAUAAAACUGAAAACUUCUCAAGUUCUGUCAAUAGCAAAUUUAAGGUAAGGAACUUUAAGCCAGGCAAAUACUAUUGUGAUAAAUGUCGAUUCUCUACAAAGGACCCGCUGCAGUACAAAAAGCACACCCUUCAACACGAGGAGAUUAAAUUCAUUUGUUCUCACUGCAGCUACAUUUCGUAUACGAAAGGAGAGUUUCAGAGGCAUUUGGUGAAACACACAGGCAUAUUUCCUUAUCAGUGUGAGUAUUGUGACUAUGGUGCUAUUAGAAAUGAUUAUAUUGUCAAACACACGAAGAGAGUACAUGAAAGGGCAGGUGCGAAACGGCCAGUCAAAGCUGUUGCCAAGCUGGAGCCAAAAAGAACCGGAACUUCAAAACAAAACCCAGAGCUUCUAAAAGCUUCCAAUCCACGGACUACAUUUCAAAAUAAGUGGUCAGACCAACUGUCAGGUUUCUCUCUCCAUGCAAAUAAAGACAAAAUGCACAAUAUCAUGUUGUUACCUGAACCAAAGGAAUACCAAAAAGAUGUAGUUUGUAUUCCAAAUAAAAUGACCCUGUCUGAGCCAAAUGAAGUCAACCUAUUUGAGAACAAAAAUGUUGAAGUAGAAGUGUUAUCCCCUGCAAAAGAACCUGUUCAGCCAGGUAUGCCAUUGACAGUUGUUGCACCAGCAGAACUAGUUGUCCCUGCAAACUGUUUAGCCCAGUUGAUAGAUGUGAAGGUUGUCAAUGGUACACAGCAGCUUGUUCUGAAACUGUUUCCGCUGGAAGAAAAUAAUUGCCUUGAAGCUGGGAGGGAUAAUGGAGGUAAUUCUGAACGUAUGGUGAAAGAGAAGGGUUCAAAUGAACAAGAAAAAGUACUUUCUGCAGAAAAAACAAAGUCACUGACAGUUGACGGGAAUGUUGGAAAACUCGUAGGCAUUGAUAGUUUUCAACCUUCAGUUCAGAAACAGCUUAAAAAUGUGAAAUGGGUAAGGUCUUAUGAUUUUAUUAUGCCAAAUUCUAGUGUGCACAACAAUGGAAAAUCCUUCAUUAAUUCGGAAACAAUUGAGGAUUUUCAGAAAAAAAAUAAUUUGUAUCCACAUAGAACUGCUUUUCCUUCCGUUGCCUUAAAAGGUCAUUCUCUAGCAUCUGUAUUUAAAAACAGUGUUUUACGUAGUCUUGGAGCUGCAUCAAACCCUUUUCCAUAUAAAGCUGCUGUUUGUUUUGCUGAAAGUGGAAGAAAUUUACACAGUAGCUCACAGCAGUUACUCCCAUUUGCUGCAUCACCUGCAACCUGUUCCUUCUCUGGAGAAAAGGGCUUAUUGCCUGUAAGUGAAAAUGACUUGGAAUCUACAAGUAAAGUCAAUAUUCCUGUAAAAGUGGUUUCCUCUAAUAGGAAGCAGGAAGAUAACCAGACAGAGGAACACAAGGCAGUUUCAACUGUAGGCCAGAUUUCCUCUCAACAUAAGAGUGAGUAUUUACAUAUAAACAUAACUGGAGAAGAUAGAUCUCAACAGCCUGGGGAUAAGCCUUUGGAAUUAAAGAAUUCUGAAAGGACUAACAACACUAAUGAUGGCCCAGUCAUCUCAUCAGUAUUUUCUCUGAGCUCUGGAUCUGAAAAUGUCCCCGAGGGCAUUAAGUGGAAUAGCUCAACGUCUAAAAUAAAGUCAAUUGAACUGUUGCGCAGAAAGAUAGCUCAGUUAAUUGAGUCCUGUGGGAAGCCGUCAUCUUUGGCUUCAAAUAGUGCACAUCGUCGCUCUGUAGGGCAGGCAUCAAAGGGAACUUCAAAAGCUACCUCUGAAGGUAUUCAAGAAAUCAACGUGUCACUCACUGGUCUUGGCCAUUCCACAGGUACUCUUCAGAAACCUCCGAAUGAUGGUGGUAUUACUGGUAAUAGACAGCUUACUCAUCAACAAAUAUAUCCACACUUUGCAGAUGGCAGUAAUAGGAAAACCAAAAGCAGAGUGGCCAGGAAGGCUCAUGUUGCCACGCCAGUGUUAAUCCCCAAAGGGGCUGUGUUGAGGGUUCUUAAUUCCUCUGAGAAUGCCCACAUCAUAGAGGCUACAUGUGAAGCACCUGUCAGCAUACCUUGCAGUGAAAGACAGUUAAUAAAACCAGUUCCAUUUUGCCCUGUGAGACAGGCGGACUCAGACUUACAGCCUUUAAGAAGUGAAAGGGGGCCAAUAGAUAUGUCCCCAAAUAUCGAGACACCUCUGCGGCCUAAACUGAGAAAAGAGAGUGCUGUCUGUAGCACCAUCCAUAGAAAAACUGGCCUCUUGUAUGGACAGCAAGGAAGCAGUGAAUUAAAUAAGCAAGGGAGACUGCUUUCCAGAAGUCUUUCUAUAAGUAGAAAUAAAACCAAACAAGUACACUUAUCCAGGAAGAAAAACAAAAUUCAAGCUGAACCUAGCCGCUGUCUCAAGGAUCCUUCAAUUUUUCAGGUUGCAAGGCAACUAAGACUGAUAGCAGCUAAGCCAGAUCAGUUGAUUAAGUGUCCCCGUCGGAACCAGCCAGUCAUUGUGUUAAACCACCCUGAUGUGGACUCGCCAGAAGUGACCAAUGUGAUGAAGGUAAUAAAUAAAUACAAAGGCAAUGUCCUCAAAGUUGUUUUAUCAGAGAGGACUAGGUGUCAGCUAGGCAUCAGACGGCAUCAUGUACGCCUGACCUACCAGAAUGCGGAAGAAGCCAGUCAAAUUAAAAGGCAAAUGAUGUUGAAAAUGAAACUCAAAAAAGUUCAUAAAAACAACUACCAGGUAGUGGAUUCCUUGCCUGAUGAUUCUUCACAGUGUGUAUUUAAGUGCUGGUUUUGUGGGCGACUGUAUGAAGACCAGGAAGAGUGGAUGAGUCAUGGCCAACGGCAUUUGAUAGAAGCAACUAGAGAUUGGGAUGUUCUUUCCUCCAAGGGCAAAUAAGUAAACAGUUACUCUUUAAAGCAAGUUAUCUUUUAGUUUAUUCUGGUUUGGAGUCCCUCCACCAAGAUUCAGUAGAAGAAAUACAGACUGUAGAAAUGAGAGGACUGCUAAUUCUUCAGAACUGUAGGAAUAUUGGGAGCUAGGAGUCUGAACCUGAAGUAUGUGAUUGGACCCCAGAAUGUAUUUGAAGGCUCUGAAAUUGUACAUGCAAAUUGGUACAUAUGCAUUUUUCUGGAGAGAGCCUGUGAAACUGAACAGAUUUUCAGUGGGAUCUGAGACUUUUCUUUGUUUAGCACCCCGUUUUCUGAGUACAUACUGAUCUUUCAUAAUCCAUUCAGAGGGGCAGAUUGAGAAUGUUUUACACAUGCUCUUCAUAUAAAUGCUACAGAAAAACCUUUGUUUUGGUGUGCACAUCCAUUUUGUUUUUGCUUUAAUUUGUGUUCUGAGUAUUUGGUGCACAAUGGAAAUUAUAUUUUCUACUUUACUGUCUUCAAUUUGGUUAUAGAGAAAUGGCCAUUCUUUUACUCCCUCCCUGGUUUUGUAAUACUCCCGAGUGUUCCGUAUAGCACAAAGAGUUUUGCUUUUACUGGCCAUUUUAAAGAAUGUUUUCAACUGCUUGCCUGAAUUUACUCCUUUCACAGCAAGUGUUAGAAGAAAGAUAACAUUUUCAAAUACUUAGCUUUUGCUUUCUUUAAAAUACAUUGGUUUAUGACAUAUGGGAAGGGAACGUACCUUUUUGCAAAGACAAAAAGAGAUUACAAAAGGAAAAUAUCUAAAACUAUUUUCUCUUUGCCCUUACCACUCCCAGAAACAUAAGUGACCAAUUUAAAAUGCUAGGGAACAGGCUUACAACAUAGGUAAAACUCGCAAACACAGUUCAAGGUAGGCUCAUAAAGUUGUGAAAAGGGUUUCAUAUGCCCUUUAGUUUUCAUUUGGGAUUCAUCCAAAGACCAUGGGUGGAUGCUGUCUUCUCUCUUCUUGAUCCCUUUGAUUCAUGGACACUAGACUCCCUUUGCCAUUUCUUCUGAACCGGCCCUCCUGUGGACUAGCACAACUUCCUUGCCCACUGUUUCUUCCUUUCUGUGCCUUUGAGACCCCUUAAGGUUUUCCCUCAUGCGAUUACUAGAAAAUGGCAGGAAUCAACAAAAUGGAGACCUCCCACUGUUUUUGCUAAAGUUACAGGAACACGAUCCCUAGUUUUCAUUGAUAGUAACGCUGUUUCUAAUUUGUCUUAACCACAUUCAUGCUUACCCUGCUGCUCAGCUUUCUCAGGGAAGCAACUCCAGGAACACUCCUUCCACUCCCCUCUCUACCAACAGAUGUCAGGACUGUCAUUUAUCUACACAUUUGUGUUCUUUAGAAAAAGGCCCACCCCCUGCACAAGCACAGCCUCUUGGGCAGAUAGGUGGCUGGGUCAGUGCUUAAGACAGGAUUCUAGUCUUCACUUGCCUGUGCAGCUGGGCGCUGACCUUCCAGGUAGAGCACAGAUGGCACAACCCCGAGGCAGCCCCAACUUGCAUUUCCCUCCCUCCAGGGGCUAUUCCUGUCUUAGGCGAUUUGUGGGGUGCAGUGAAUGAAACUAAAGAGUUGUUGCACCUGAAAAAGACACCAGUGAUUGUUUAUUGGGUAGUCGAUUGGAGACUUUGAUUUUUUUUUUUUUUUUUCACAUGGGAAAGUCUUAGAUUCCAGUAGAUGGAAUUGCAAUCCUUUGCAGUUUGUUCUCAUUACAGAUAAUCAACAUUUCUUUUGUAUAAUUCAAUACAUGAUCAUCAAGUUAAUUGGUAAAUUUUUAUUGAAAUUUAAAACUUGCAUUUUUAUAUAUGUGUAUGUGUACACAUAAAAAUAUUUUUUACCAUAUGAAAAUUGCAGUAGCUAAUUUUCUGAUUUCCUAUUUUAUAAUGAUACAUGGGCUGGAAAAAUGUAGAACGUUUUUAUAUUCUAGAAAUUUAUUUUGGAAGUACAUUUUUAUAAGGGUCUAAUCUCACUUUUGGAAAAUGAAAGCACAGGAAUGAUGGGGUCUGGUUUAUGUGAACAAGUGAGUAGAAACCCCUUUGGAUCAUUUUAUUACUGCAUUUUUAUUUGGUGCUUUUUAGGAAGUAGAUCUUUGGUACCACUUCACUACGUAGAGCAUUCGAAGUUUUAUCCAUGUUAUAUAUUGUACUCCUGUGGCAUGAAAAAUAGCUCCCAAGAUAUAGAGAGGAGAGGAGUGAAGAAAAGGCUGUGGUUUUUUUUUGUUUUGUUUUGUUUGCCACUUUUUUAUCUCCUAUUCCUCACCACAUAGUGCUUUUUCCUGAAAAGCUGGACUGAGAAUUGGCCUUGAAUCAGGUCAGAGUGUUAACUGUCAACAUGAAGUAUUUUCACUUCGCAGCAUCAACUUUCAAGCAUAAGUAAAAACACAACUUGCAUACUUUGAUGGAGCUUAAUUGUGUGAGUAGAAUAUGUAGCAAAGCUUUUUAGGAUUUUCAGAACUAGAAUACUUUUUAAGGAAUUAAAAGUGUUUCUGGAAGUCAAAAAUGGGAAAGCAAAAAGUAGCUGUCCUCCCUAAAGAGCUUUAGAAGAUAGCUUAACCUGUAGGUACAUGUUAUGAAAUAAACACAUUUCUAACAAUACAAGGGAGUAGGGGCAGACCUGUGUUGAGUAUUUGUGUGGGUUCUUAAUUUUGAAGGACCUCCAAUCACUACAUUUUGUUAAUACUGCCAAUAAAAUCAUUUUCAACUUAUUUUUUAAAGUAGGUUUUCUUACUUUGGUGGACCAGAAGUGAGAGAUUGUUAUAUUUAGGAUAUAGGCAAAUACAGUAAAAGUUAAAAAAAAAAAACCUGACCCAAAGUAUACUCUGAUAGACUAUAUUAUAUUCAAUUUUGUAUCCCCAGUCGAGAACAUCUUGUAAGCCUUCAUUAAGGGCCACCUGCUGUCUGUUGAACUAGACUGAACAAAAUAUAUUUUCUCACAAGCUCCAUCCCUUUUUCUUUAGGACAUGUUAUAUAUAAUCCAUCUCAGAAGUUGAAGAUGUGAUGUUGCUCGGCCUUUGGAAUAAUUUUUAAAUCUGUAAAUGUCUAUAUGAGCAGAAACAAAACAUUGUGUAACAUGUUUUAAGCAUUAUUGUAAUUCCUGUGUUAACAGUUUGUGUGUCUGCUGCUCUGGUUUUGAAACAUGUUUGUAUAUAGAUACAGGAGUUGGCAUAAAUUUUGUUAAAUAAAGCAACAAAAAUUUUCUUUGCCCUUUGA